GUCCCUGUCUUGAGGUCUAAUGGCGGACGCCAGUAUGUUGGAGUUGGUGGUGGCUUAAGUUUUGAAGGGAGGUAGCAUCCGUUGGAUAUCCACACCAUCCUUCUCGCUGCAGGCUUUCUUGGACUCCGUACUGUUGGUGUAACCAAGGCCUGGAGGUCUGGGUGGCUCAGGUUUCCUGCAGCCAUGUUUCUGUACAACUUAACCUUGCAGAGAGCCACUGGCAUCAGCUUUGCCAUUCAUGGAAACUUUUCUGGAACCAAACAACAAGAAAUUGUUGUUUCCCGUGGGAAGAUCUUGGAGCUGCUUCGCCCAGACCCCAACACUGGCAAAGUACAUACCCUACUCACUGUGGAAGUAUUCGGUGUUAUCCGGUCACUCAUGGCCUUUAGGCUGACAGGUGGCACCAAAGACUACAUUGUAGUUGGCAGUGACUCUGGUCGAAUUGUUAUUUUGGAAUACCAGCCAUCUAAGAAUAUGUUUGAGAAGAUUCACCAAGAAACCUUUGGCAAGAGUGGAUGCCGUCGCAUCGUUCCUGGCCAGUUCUUAGCUGUGGAUCCCAAAGGGCGAGCCGUUAUGAUUAGUGCCAUUGAGAAACAGAAAUUGGUGUAUAUUUUGAACAGAGAUGCUGCAGCCCGACUUACCAUUUCAUCUCCCCUGGAAGCCCACAAAGCAAACACUUUAGUGUAUCAUGUAGUUGGAGUAGAUGUCGGAUUUGAAAAUCCAAUGUUUGCUUGUCUGGAAAUGGAUUAUGAGGAAGCAGACAAUGAUCCAACAGGGGAAGCAGCAGCUAAUACCCAGCAGACACUUACUUUCUAUGAGCUAGACCUUGGUUUAAAUCAUGUGGUCCGAAAAUACAGUGAACCUUUGGAGGAACACGGCAACUUCCUUAUUACAGUUCCAGGAGGGUCAGAUGGUCCAAGUGGAGUACUGAUCUGCUCUGAAAACUAUAUUACUUACAAGAACUUUGGUGACCAGCCAGAUAUCCGCUGUCCAAUUCCCAGGAGGCGGAAUGACCUGGAUGACCCUGAAAGAGGAAUGAUUUUUGUCUGCUCUGCAACCCAUAAAACCAAAUCGAUGUUCUUCUUUUUGGCUCAAACUGAGCAGGGAGAUAUCUUUAAGAUCACUUUGGAGACAGAUGAAGAUAUGGUUACUGAGAUCCGGCUCAAAUAUUUUGAUACUGUACCCGUUGCUGCUGCCAUGUGUGUGCUUAAAACAGGGUUCCUUUUUGUAGCAUCAGAAUUUGGAAACCAUUACUUAUAUCAAAUUGCACAUCUUGGAGAUGAUGAUGAAGAACCUGAGUUUUCAUCAGCCAUGCCUCUGGAAGAAGGAGACACAUUCUUUUUUCAGCCAAGACCACUUAAAAACCUUGUGCUGGUUGAUGAGUUGGACAGCCUCUCUCCCAUUCUGUUUUGCCAGAUAGCUGAUCUGGCCAAUGAAGAUACUCCACAGUUGUAUGUGGCCUGUGGUAGGGGACCCCGAUCAUCUCUGAGAGUCCUAAGACAUGGACUUGAGGUGUCAGAAAUGGCUGUUUCUGAGCUACCUGGUAACCCCAACGCUGUCUGGACAGUGCGUCGACACAUUGAAGAUGAGUUUGAUGCCUACAUCAUUGUGUCUUUCGUGAAUGCCACCCUAGUGUUGUCCAUUGGAGAAACUGUAGAAGAAGUGACUGACUCUGGGUUCCUGGGGACCACCCCGACCUUGUCCUGCUCCUUAUUAGGAGAUGAUGCCUUGGUGCAGGUCUAUCCAGAUGGCAUUCGGCACAUACGAGCAGACAAGAGAGUCAAUGAGUGGAAGACCCCUGGAAAGAAAACAAUUGUGAAGUGUGCAGUGAACCAGCGACAAGUGGUGAUUGCCCUGACAGGAGGAGAGCUGGUCUAUUUCGAGAUGGAUCCUUCAGGACAGCUGAAUGAGUACACAGAACGGAAGGAGAUGUCAGCAGAUGUGGUGUGCAUGAGUCUGGCCAAUGUACCCCCUGGAGAGCAGCGGUCUCGCUUCCUGGCUGUGGGGCUUGUGGACAACACUGUCAGAAUCAUCUCCCUGGAUCCCUCAGACUGUUUGCAACCUCUAAGCAUGCAGGCUCUCCCAGCCCAGCCUGAGUCCUUGUGUAUCGUGGAAAUGGGUGGGACUGAGAAGCAGGAUGAGCUGGGUGAGAGGGGCUCGAUUGGCUUCCUAUACCUGAAUAUUGGGCUACAGAACGGUGUGCUGCUGAGGACUGUCUUGGACCCUGUCACUGGGGAUUUGUCUGAUACUCGCACUCGGUACCUGGGGUCCCGUCCUGUGAAGCUCUUCCGAGUCCGAAUGCAAGGCCAGGAGGCAGUAUUGGCCAUGUCAAGCCGCUCAUGGUUGAGCUAUUCUUACCAAUCUCGCUUCCAUCUCACCCCACUGUCUUACGAGACACUGGAAUUUGCAUCGGGUUUUGCCUCGGAACAGUGUCCCGAGGGCAUUGUGGCCAUCUCCACCAACACCCUACGGAUUUUGGCAUUAGAGAAGCUCGGUGCUGUCUUCAAUCAAGUAGCCUUCCCACUGCAGUACACACCCAGGAAAUUUGUCAUCCACCCUGAGAGUAACAACCUUAUUAUCAUUGAAACGGACCACAAUGCCUACACUGAGGCCACGAAAGCUCAGAGAAAGCAGCAGAUGGCAGAGGAAAUGGUGGAAGCAGCAGGGGAGGAUGAGCGGGAGCUGGCCGCAGAGAUGGCAGCAGCAUUCCUCAAUGAAAACCUCCCUGAAUCCAUCUUUGGAGCUCCCAAGGCUGGCAAUGGGCAGUGGGCCUCUGUGAUCCGAGUGAUGAAUCCCAUUCAAGGGAACACACUGGACCUUGUCCAGCUGGAACAGAAUGAGGCAGCUUUUAGUGUGGCUGUGUGCAGGUUUUCCAACACUGGUGAAGACUGGUAUGUGCUGGUGGGUGUGGCCAAGGACCUGAUACUAAACCCCCGAUCUGUGGCAGGGGGCUUCGUCUAUACUUACAAGCUUGUGAACAAUGGGGAAAAACUGGAGUUUUUGCACAAGACUCCUGUGGAAGAGGUCCCUGCUGCUAUUGCCCCAUUCCAGGGGAGGGUGUUGAUUGGUGUGGGGAAGCUGUUGCGUGUCUAUGACCUGGGAAAGAAGAAGUUACUCCGAAAAUGUGAGAAUAAGCAUAUUGCCAAUUAUAUCUCUGGGAUCCAGACUAUCGGACAUAGGGUAAUUGUAUCUGAUGUCCAAGAAAGUUUCAUCUGGGUUCGCUACAAGCGUAAUGAAAACCAGCUUAUCAUCUUUGCUGAUGAUACCUACCCCCGAUGGGUCACUACAGCCAGCCUCCUGGACUAUGACACUGUGGCUGGGGCAGACAAGUUUGGCAACAUAUGUGUGGUGAGGCUCCCACCUAACACCAAUGAUGAAGUAGAUGAGGAUCCUACAGGAAACAAAGCCCUGUGGGACCGUGGCUUGCUCAAUGGGGCCUCCCAGAAGGCAGAGGUGAUCAUGAACUACCAUGUCGGGGAGACGGUGCUGUCCUUGCAGAAGACCACGCUGAUCCCUGGAGGCUCAGAAUCACUUGUCUAUACCACCUUGUCUGGAGGAAUUGGCAUCCUUGUGCCAUUCACGUCCCAUGAGGACCAUGACUUCUUCCAGCAUGUGGAAAUGCACCUGCGGUCUGAACAUCCCCCUCUCUGUGGGCGGGACCACCUCAGCUUUCGCUCCUACUACUUCCCUGUGAAGAAUGUGAUUGAUGGAGACCUCUGUGAGCAGUUCAAUUCCAUGGAACCCAACAAACAAAAGAACGUCUCUGAAGAACUGGACCGAACCCCACCCGAAGUGUCCAAGAAACUCGAGGAUAUCCGGACCCGCUACGCCUUCUGAGCCCUCCUUUCCCGGUGGGGCUUGCCAGAGACUGUGUGUUUUGUUUCCCCCACCACCAUCACUGCCACCUGGCUUCUGCCAUGUGGCAGGAGGGUGACUGGAUAAUUAAGACUGCAUUAUGAAAGUCAACAGCUCUUUCCCCUCAGCUCUUCUCCUGGAAUGACUGGCUUCCCCUCAAAUUGGCACUGAGAUUUGCUACACUUCUCCCCACCUGGUACAUGAUACAUGACCCCAGGUUCCAGUGUAGAACCUGAGUCCCCCAUUCCCCAAAGCCAUCCCUGCAUUGAUAUGUCUUGACUCUCCUGUCUACUUUUGCACACACCCUUAAUUUUUAAUUGGUUUUCUUGUAAAUACAGUUUUGUACAAUGUUAUCUCUGUGGGAGGAAGGAGGCAGGCUGUGGUGGGACUGGGUAGGGUAUAGUAUCACUCCUGAGUUCCACUGCUCUAGAAUCUAACCAGAAAUAGAAACCUAGUUUUUAAGGUGACUGGCAUCCAUGUGUCUUGUUCUGGAGAUGAGGAUGUAGGUGGGAGGUUUGAACCCAAGUUAGAGCAGGAAGAACUGAGUAGACUCCUUCCUUCCAGAUACCGACUUGGACUUGCGGCACUCUGUGGCUCCCCACCCCCAGGUCUGUGGUGGUUUCUUUGUUUUUUCCUGGUUCUUUUUGCUGUGCUGAUGAAACAUGACCUCAAUAACCAUGUGUAUACCCACCCCUCUUCCCACUGGGUAUUGAGGAAGGGUGGCUGAUUCUUCCUCCUCUUCUACUCUGAGGAUGUUAGUAUGGGGAUUUUAGCAUGAAUUCUAGCUGGGGAGUCUUAACAGAUGCCCCUUUUACUGAUACAGCACCUAAAGCGAUCUUUGGCUCCAUAGGACCAUAGGAAGGGUCAGUACAGAAGAACCUAGAUACUGCCCUGCCCCUGAGAACUGUGUAUAUGUGGGGCCUGUCUGCAGCACCCAUCUCAGGUGGGUUCCAGAGGGCCUUUAGGGUAUAAUGAGAGCCUGUUAGGUGGAAGAGGCCCAGUUCCAGAAAUGUUCCAGCCCACCCCUGAGAAUUCCUCCUGUUUAGUUGUGUGGGAAGCCCUCGUCUUCCAGGCUGUCCUUGCGCCUUGAACCUGGAGAAGUGAGCUCACUGUUCUCAAUACUUCACAAAUGUAAAACUUUCUUUCGUCUGCAUGUGCUCAGCCAUCUAAAUUGAGCAAAUGAUCUGGUGAGCACUGGGUUAGAAUCAGGAAUGGUGGAAUACAAUCUGAACCUCUCAGAGCCCAGAACAGAGGGUUCCUGACACUGUGACACUGUCUCCUGGAACUAAGUAUCUCUUGAAUCAUGACUUGGUUUUAGAUCAGUCAAGAGAGACCCAGGUUUUGCCAGGAAUCGAAUCCCUAAAUAACAUGUUUUUUUCUCACUUAGCUCAUGAAUUUGCAUAGUAGACAGUAGUUCUGAAUUAGAUUUUGAAAACCUAAUUUCAGGGCUCAUUUUUUCCUGUGGCCCUAAAUCCAUUCUAUCAAAUUGUGUGAUACUGACAUGCAGUCAUCUGAGGAACUCAGCGUAGAUACUUGAGCAGCUCCUCGCCUCUUUUCUAACUCAAGUUUGACUAAAAUACAUACACUCCGUACAGAAGGUAGGGGGUUAUGUAAGAAAGGAAAACCUAAUCUAUGGAAUCAGGAGUUGUCACCACCGAGCUUCCUCUGGAAGUCUGCCCAUCAGCUUGCUUGUUCUCUGUUAAGAGGAAGGGCUAGGACAAGGAUUUGGGCUUGAAUAUGUGGAAAGGAAUUUUCAUAGUUGUUGCUGCAGGACCUACAAAAGUUUAAAAUUAGAUUGGAUGUGACUCAAUGACAAGUCCCAUCUGUGUAAUUGUUAAGGGGACCUGAUUGACUCCUGUGGUUUGAUUGAGCAACCAGGUAAAUAGAGACCUCUCUCCAGCUUUGGCAAAACCCAUCAGAGGCUGCUGCAGAACUCAGACAGAGGGAUCUGCCCUUGGGUUUGCUUCCAUCCUGUUCCAUUGCUAAGCCCUUGUGACUUGGAUCCUAGGACUGAAAAGUUUUUAGCUGCCUCAGCUUUCCCCUGACCUUACUGGCAGAGGUUCUGCAGAUGUUUCCUUUGGAAGAUCUCUUGCCAAGAAUAGCAUUCCUUUGGAGGAGGGGGGUUCUAGUUGGAAUGUUGCUUUUCUUGGUUAGUGUAAAUGUAUUGCUAGUGAGACAGCUGCCGGCGCUGGAAAAGGCUCGUCUCACAGGGAGAGUGCUGGUCCCCAGAAUGUGUGCUGUUCCCACGCUGCUGCCUUUCUUGAGCUUGUUAGAGGAAAGCCAGAAAGGCAUUCAGAUGGGAUCAGUCUGGCUUUCAAAUUUUUUUUAAUUCCUAAGUUCUGUUUUAUUUUUUAAUUUUUUAAAAAAAAUUUUAUUAGAGACAGUCUCUCUCUCUUGCCUAGCUGGGAGUGCAGUGGAGUGAUCAUAGCUCACUGAGGCUUGAACUCCUGGGCUCGAGCAAUCCACCUCAGCCUCCAGAGUAGGGGAGACUACAGAUGUGUGCCACCAUACUCAGCUAAUUUUUAAACUUUUGUAGAGACAGGGUCUCCCUGUGUUGCCCAGGCUGGCCUCGAACUCCUGACCUCAAAAAAUCUUCCUGCCUUGGCCUCCCAAAGCACUGGGAUUAUAGGUGUGAGCCAUUGCGCCUGGUCAUAAAUUCUUGUUUUUUUGUUUGUUUGUUUAUUAGAGAUGGAAUCUCUCUCUCUUGACCAGGCUAGAGGGCUGUGGUGCGAUCUCAGCCCACUGCAACCUCUAUCUCCUGAGCUCAAGCGAUCCUCCUUAGCUUCCCAAAUAGCUGGAACUACAGGCAUGUGCCAUCACGUCCAGCUAAUUUUUGUAUUUUUAGUAGAGAAGGUUUUACCAUGUUGGACAGGGUGGUCUCGAACUCCUGGCCUAAAGUGGUCCACCUAGCUCAGCCUACCAAAGUGCUGUGAUUACAGGCGUGAGCCACCAUGCCCAGCCUCUAAAUUCUGUUUUCUAUUCAAAGUAAAAAUGACAUGUGUUUGAGUCAUCCACUUGCUCAUUUGCAUAUGGAAUAUUGUAUGUGAAUAUUUUAUUACACCCUUAAAAUUAAUUUUCAAGGGCUAUAUGUAGAGCUCAGAAGAAACAUCUCUGCUGCUGAAAUCAAACCUGGUCCAAAAAACGUCACAACGGAGGAAAGGAAUAGAUGGCUCUCGAGGACAAGAUAGGGACUCUUAAAACACCUGCUUGGCCAUGGUUGAUUGACAUUUGAGUGAUCUGGUAGCCCAACACACCCUGUGAAGUUCAGGUGAACUGAAAUGGGCAGGUGUAGGCUACACACCAGUCUGAACCAGCACAACCAAGAGUUGUUUCUCUUUUUUUUCUUUUUCUUUUUCUUUUUUUUCUUUUUUUUUUUUUUUUUUUUGAGAUGAAGUCUUACUCUGUUGCCCAGGCUAGAGUACAGAGGCACAAUCUCGGCUCACCACAGCCUCCGCCUCCUGGGUUCAAGCAAUUCUCCUGCCUCAGCCUCCCAAGUAGCUGGGACUACAGGCAUGCACCACCAUGCCUGGCUAAUUUUUGUAUUUUUAGUAGAGAUGGGGUUUCACCAUGUUGGCCAGGCUGGUUUCGAACUCGUGACCUCAGGUGAUCCACCCACCUUGGUCUCCCAAAGCGCUGGGAUUACAGGCGUGAGCCACUGCACUUGGCCAGGAGCUGUUUAAGCCAUCAGGAGACAUGCUGACCCACUAGAAGAGGCUGCUACGCUCAUUUCUUCCACAAACGUUUACUGGGCACCUACCAUGAACCACCACCUCCCAGCUCUGUUCUGCACCCAGAGGUUGGAGGAGAGUUUAUAACCAGGCAGUCUCUGUCGCUGUGAGGUUGGUGGUGAGGUGAGUCUGCCAGAGGGCCUGCCACCAGUUUCAGAAGAGCCUGCAGCCUGCAUCUGAUUUCCUCAGCCACAACCUUGGGACUUCAGGAAAAAUCAGAAGGUCCCAAGUCUGAAAAAUGAAGAGGUGGGGAGUGGGCAGCAGGGGUUUUAGGUCAGGAAAUGGUAGGAAACCUGUAGUUGUGGCUCAUAAUCCUAGUGGGAUAUUAGAACCCUCUUCAUUUGUCAGAACAGAUUCCUGGGGUCUGCUCCCAAUUAUUCACACGGUGGUUCAUGCCUGGUAAUCCCAGCACUUUGGGCGGCCAGAGGCAGGCAGAUUGCUUGAGCCCAGAAGUUUAAGACCAGCCUAGGAAACAGACCCCAUCUCUACAAAAAAUUCAAAAAGCCGGGCGUGAAGCCCUGUUUUUUUUUUUUUAAAAAAAGAGUCUGCUGGUGAUGUCUGGGCAUGUGUCUGCUUCACAGUCCAGUGUUAUGAUCAGUAGCUGUGAUGGACAAUGAACAUUGCUGCUUGUUCAAAAUGAAGAAAAAAAAUAUCAAAGAAAACCAGGUUUGGAAGUUUCAGAUUUGGAAAAGGAGCUGGGCCAGCCCAUCUGGAAUAGCUGAGGGGCCCUGUUAGCCCCACCCUACCCCACCCCACCCCCGUAUGCAGCAUCUCUGGCGGUGCCCAGAGGCAAGCCCCCUUCAGUUUCCCACCUCUCACUCUGCCUUCCAGAGCCUAGUCAAGUUUUAAAUUCCCAGGUCCACUCAGCAGAACUUGCUCCCUUCUCUGACUGCAGUCUCAUAAUGAAAGGAGAGGUGCUUUCAGUUGGGUCAUUUGGUAGCGUUUAGGCUUAGAAGUUACUAAUUUGGAGCCGUGAGUAUAUGUGUAUAAGCUAGUAACACGUGAUGGUCAAGGGAAGUACUACCAUUUCCUGUGGGUUAUUAGGGCCUCCAGCUGUUAUGAGGACACACUGGGGAAUCUCAGCUUUAGGGAGUCGAUGAUGUAACUGGAGAAAGGCAAUGCUGCCCUCAUAAAGCAAUCAGAAACGAGAUUCCACCUGCCAAAUGCCAAGAGGCAGCAAAGUCCAUGAAGAGAGCACUGUAUACAGUCAGAUGACCUGGGCUCACUAGCCUCUAAGCAUAGUCUUGGUUUCCUGCCUGUAAAUUGGUAGAAUAAGACUGAUUUACUGGGCCUGGCAUGGUGGCUCACACCUGUAAUCCCAGCACUUUGAGAGGCUGAGGCAGGAGGAUCCCUUGAGCCCAGGAGUUUGAGACCAGCCUGGGCAACAUGACAAAACCCCAUCUCUCCAAAAAUACAAAAAUUAGCCAGGCAUGGUGGUGCACACUUGUAGUCCCAGUAAUUAGGGGGCUGAGACAGGAGGAUCACUUCAGCCUAUGAGUUUGAGGCUGCAGUGAGCUGUGAUUGCGCCACUACACUCCAGCCUGGAUGACAGGACGAAACCUGUCUCAAAAACACCAAAAAACAAAAACCGGUCUCCUGGGGUCAUGGUAGCACAAACGCACAUGACUGAGUGCUCAGGGGUUCUGAGGCUUGUCCGCUGACCUGGGGCUCUGGCCCUGGGAGAUCUGGGGGACCUGCUGUCCUAUAUGUGAUGCUUUGAAAGAAAGGGGCAUCAUUCCAAGCCAAGAGGCCCCAGAGAGGGCACCGUGCGGUGUUCAGGCUUCUGUGAGGCCCCAGUGAGAUCCUGUGGCUGUGCCCCCAUCACCUCCACCCACUCUGCCCUCCCACUAGCUGCCCAACGGAUGAAUCAACGCCUUGGCAGAGUUUUCCAGCAGGGCCUUGCAGAGAGUGUGUGUGACCUGUGUGGCCACUGCCUUGGGGACGGGUGAGGAGUUAGCCUGGAACAUUCCAGCGUGGGCAUUAUUGUCCUGUUGCAAGUUCAGGGCAAAACCAGGAAUCCAGUUUUGUCGAUCCAAUUGAGAAAACAUUUCAUGAACAACUACUUGUGGCAUGCAUUGGCACUCGGAAUAAAGCGCACUAUUGUCACUA